AGACCCUUUUCCGGCUGACUUCUGAGAAGGUUGCGCAGCAGCUGUGCCCGGCAGUCUAGAGGCGCAGAAGAGGAAGCCAUCGCCUGGCCCCGGCUCUCUGGACCUUGUCUCGCUCGGGAGCGGAAACAGCGGCAGCCAGAGCAUAAAAUACACAAGAGGAUUUUUAUGGAAUGGCUCCUUGUUACAAGGUACUUUGCAUUUAUAAUCAGCCACAGUCACCUCAGUUUCAUCCCGUAUCUUACAAGUAUGAUGUGCUGUAUACUCAAAGCCUCACCACCUGCUUGCCCCACCCAUUUGCUUAAAUGUAUCAAUUUUUUCUAAGCUUAACUUUUACCAAAACUGGAGUUCAACAGAUGAAUAUUUUUCCUUCUUAGAUGUUAACUAAACAUUUUUAAAGGUACAAAAUUUAUGUACAAACAUAACCCAAAUGACAUGGAAGUUACUUGAUUUGUGACUUACCUCUGUAAUGUUCCCCUGGCCUACUUGAAAUUCCUACCUUUCCUCUAGUCUAGUAUCUUAUUCUCAGUUAUUCGGAGGAAGUUAGGGACCUAGAAUUCUUGUUUUCAGAGCAGUAGAAUUUUGCUAACAUAAUUCAAAACAUUUAUCCCUAUCUUGGGGCUUGAAGAGAAUGUGAAAUGCUUUAUCUUCUGUUUUGAGGGAAUGAGGGAAGGAGCUUGUUCUUAGGCAAUUAACAAGUAAAUUUAAAUAAAUAAUCCAAAUCUGGUGUGGGUAAACAAAUUUUAGUUUUAGGAACUUUCAAAAUUAAGUAUGCUUCCCCUUUGGGUUCCAGAUUUUACAGUAAUACUUUUUGAAAGCAGUAAGAUAAAAAUUUCAGGACCUCAAGAGAUGGGUCAAAAGAGUUUCACUGUAAUAUGAAUUUUGAAGCCAGAACUGGAAAUCCCCUGUGCUGUGUCUUCCUCUUCGUGGUAGUAGAGGUUACAGUUAUCAAAUAGUCCAGAGAAGCAAUGGGAACUUAUGAUUUCUGAUAGAAAAAUUUUAACAGAGAUGUACUUGUAUGCAAAUAAUAUAUGAUGCCUCAGUUUCCUCCAAAGUCUUAGUUAACAGAGUUAGAAAAAAUCAGAUUAUAUUUGAAGUUCUGUGUUCAUACUGGAGUAAUUAUUAUUCCAAUGGUACAAUAUACAACAUAACUUUAUUACAUUUUUUGGUACAGCAUAAAGAUGAUUUUCCCUUUCUCUGAGUAUUUCUGAAAUUUAAAAUGAAAUAAGUGUGGUAGAAGCCAUUAUUUAUGAAUUAUCAUGCUAAAUUAAUUAACUCAUUAAUUCAUUCAGGGCACACCCAGUUAUUCCCCAAACUGAGUGAUGUAUUUCUGGGAAUAGACUUAUUAAGCUUGAGAAAACCCAAAGGAUCAUUAUAACAGCAAACAGGAAUGUAGGCAUCCACAUAGUGGAUGACUUUAGUGACCUGGCACACAGUGCCUUAUCUACUUGGCACAUGUACAGGUACAAGGAACACUUAACAUUUUGCACCAGAGCUUAUUACAUACCACUUUCAAUGCUUGAGAUAUUAUAUAAAUGCUAAAAUUCUAAAACCUAUAGUAAAGCAAAGACCCAGAUUUUAUACUGCAGUAGUUUUGCCAGUAAGUCUCAUCCUCACUAACUUAUCUUUUAAGAUUAAAAAUAAUGUAACCAAGUGGGAAGAAAAAGAGCAAAUAUGAACAAAUUGUCAUUGUUUUAGAAUCUGCUUCUUUUCCUUUCCGGUAUUUCUGUGCAAGGAGAGAAUGAUCUCUGACCUUGUGAAAGGCAAAUACCAUGUGUAUUCAUGGUUGUUAUUCAUUUGGCAACGACUUGAAACUCAUGACACUCCCUGCUGAAGAUCCUCCACCUAUUCUUAACAGCUGGGCUCCCCAGCUCCUGGAUCACCAACCAGUACCAGUCUGUGGCCUGUUAGGAACUGGGCUUGUACAGCAGGAGCUGAGCAGCUGGAGAGUGAGCAAAGUUUCAUCUGUAUUGACAGCUGCUCCCCAUCGCUCACAUACAUUACCACCUGAGCUCAACCUCCUGUCAGAUCAGCAGUGGCAUUAGAUUCUCAUAGGAGCAAGAACCCUAUUGUGAACUGCAUGUGUGAGGGAUCUAGGUUGCGCACUCCUUAUGAGAAUCUAAUGCCUGAUGAUCGGUCACUGUCUCCCAUCACCCCCACAUGGGACUGUCUAGUUGCGGGAAAACAAGCUCAGGGCUCCCACUGAUUCUACCUUAUAAUGAAUUGUAUAAUCCUUUUGUUAUAUAUUACAAUGUAAUAAUAAUAGAAAUAAAGUGCACAAUAAAUGUAAUGCGCUUGAAUCAUCCCAAAACCAUCCCCUGCUUCACUGGUCCAUGUCUUCCACAAAACCGGUCCCUGGUGCCAAAAAGGUUGGGGACCACUGUUUACCAGGAUGCAUAGCAUGGGUUUAUGAAUUCCCUAUCUUUGCAGCACAUCCUUUAUUUCUGGCUUGCAUGGGACUUGAAAGCCUAAAACAACUAAAUGCUAAGAAAAAUUAUUUUUAAAAUGAUGACAAAAAUAUUUUCUAUUUCAGAUGUAUAGAUCUGCAAUCCAGAAACUAUGAAUUUUUUUCAGACCACAUAAACCCAUUUUGAAUUAUUCAACCAUUGCUGAACUUCUUGAAACUGUUUUAAUCAUGGACAAACAAAACUCACAGAUGAAUGCUUCUCACCCGGAAACAAACUUGCCAGUUGGGUAUCCUCCUCAGUAUCCACCGACAGCAUUCCAAGGACCUCCAGGAUAUAGUGGCUACCCUGGGCCCCAGGUCAGCUACCCACCCCCACCAGCCGGCCAUUCAGGUCCUGGCCCAGCUGGCUUUCCUGUCCCAAAUCAGCCAGUGUAUAAUCAGCCAGUAUAUAAUCAGCCAGUUGGAGCUGCAGGGGUACCAUGGAUGCCAGCGCCACAGCCUCCAUUAAACUGUCCACCUGGAUUAGAAUAUUUAAGUCAGAUAGAUCAGAUACUGAUUCAUCAGCAAAUUGAACUUCUGGAAGUUUUAACAGGUUUUGAAACUAAUAACAAAUAUGAAAUUAAGAACAGCUUUGGACAGAGGGUUUACUUUGCAGCGGAAGAUACUGAUUGCUGUACCCGAAAUUGCUGUGGGCCAUCUAGACCUUUUACCUUGAGGAUUAUUGAUAAUAUGGGUCAAGAAGUCAUAACUCUGGAGAGACCACUAAGAUGUAGCAGCUGUUGUUGUCCCUGCUGCCUUCAGGAGAUAGAAAUCCAAGCUCCUCCUGGUGUACCAAUAGGUUAUGUUAUUCAGACUUGGCACCCAUGUCUACCAAAGUUUACAAUUCAAAAUGAGAAAAGAGAGGAUGUACUAAAAAUAAGUGGUCCAUGUGUUGUGUGCAGCUGUUGUGGAGAUGUUGAUUUUGAGAUUAAAUCUCUUGAUGAACAGUGUGUGGUUGGCAAAAUUUCCAAGCACUGGACUGGAAUUUUGAGAGAGGCAUUUACAGACGCUGAUAACUUUGGAAUCCAGUUCCCUUUAGACCUUGAUGUUAAAAUGAAAGCUGUAAUGAUUGGUGCCUGUUUCCUCAUUGACUUCAUGUUUUUUGAAAGCACUGGCAGCCAGGAACAAAAAUCAGGAGUGUGGUAGUGGAUUAGUGAAAGUCUCCUCAGGAAAUCUGAAGUCUGUAUAUUGAUUGAGACUAUCUAAACUCAUACCUGUAUGAAUUAAGCUGUAAGGCCUGUAGCUCUGGUUGUAUACUUUUGCUUUUCAAAUUAUAGUUUAUCUUCUGUAUAACUGAUUUAUAAAGGUUUUUGUACAUUUUUUAAUACUCAUUGUCAAUUUGAGAAAAAGGACAUAUGAGUUUUUGCAUUUAUUAAUGAAACUUCCUUUGAAAAACUGCUUUGAAUUAUGAUCUCUGAUUCAUUGUCCAUUUUACUACCAAAUAUUAACUAAGGCCUUAUUAAUUUUUAUAUAAAUUAUAUCUUGUCCUAUUAAAUCUAGUUACAAUUUAUUUCAUGCAUAAGAGCUAAUGUUAUUUUGCAAAUGCCAUAUAUUCAAAAAAGCUCAAAGAUAAUUUUCUUUACUAUUAUGUUCAAAUAAUAUUCAAUAUGCAUAUUAUCUUUAAAAAGUUAAAUGUUUUUUUAAUCUUCAAGAAAUCAUGCUACACUUAACUUCUCCUAGAAGCUAAUCUAUACCAUAAUAUUUUCAUAUUCACAAGAUAUUAAAUUACCAAUUUUCAAAUUAUUGUUAGUAAAGAACAAAAUGAUUCUCUCCCAAAGAAAGACACAUUUUAAAUACUCCUUCACUCUAAAACUCUGGUAUUAUAACUUUUGAAAGUUAAUAUUUCUACAUGAAAUGUUUAGCUCUUACACUCUAUCCUUCCUAGAAAAUGGUAAUUGAGAUUACUCAGAUAUUAAUUAAAUACAAUAUCAUAUAUAUAUUCACAGAGUAUAAACCUAAAUAAUGAUCUAUUAGAUUCAAAUAUUUGAAAUAAAAACUUGAUUUUUUUGUA